GAGAGAGUGUAAUAUGGCGAAGACCUACGAUUACCUGUUCAAGCUGCUGCUGAUCGGGGACUCGGGGGUGGGGAAGACCUGUGUCCUGUUCCGCUUCUCCGAGGACGCCUUCAACUCCACUUUUAUCUCCACCAUAGGAAUUGACUUUAAAAUUAGGACCAUAGAGCUCGAUGGCAAGAGAAUUAAACUGCAGAUAUGGGACACAGCCGGUCAGGAACGGUUUCGGACGAUCACAACGGCCUACUACAGGGGUGCAAUGGGCAUCAUGCUGGUCUACGACAUCACCAACGAGAAGUCCUUCGACAACAUCCGGAACUGGAUUCGCAACAUUGAGGAGCACGCCUCUGCAGACGUCGAAAAGAUGAUACUCGGGAACAAGUGUGAUGUGAAUGACAAGAGACAAGUUUCCAAGGAACGGGGAGAAAAGCUGGCCCUCGACUAUGGAAUCAAGUUCAUGGAGACCAGCGCGAAGGCCAACAUCAAUGUGGAAAAUGCAUUUUUCACUCUCGCCAGAGAUAUCAAAGCAAAAAUGGACAAAAAAUUGGAAGGCAACAGCCCCCAGGGGAGCAACCAGGGAGUCAAAAUCACACCGGACCAGCAGAAGAGGAGCAGCUUUUUCCGAUGUGUUCUUCUGUGAGGAACACCGCCUUACUCUGAGCCUCGCUCAGCCCAGCUGACUGUGCCUGUUCUGAGUGAGCCCCUCACUCAGCCGGGGCCCUCCCACCUCCAACGCCCCGCCCACGCCGCGGCCACCGGGCCCACGGCCACCAGAAUGCAAUUGAGAAAUCGUUUAUUUUAGUAACUGUCUGAUCUUUUUCAACUUUGGAGAUGGAAUAAGUUAAAAAUUUGCUAUUUUUCCUGUAACAUCUGCUGAACGGGCCCACCCACACGUUGUAUAUUCAGAGAGAGAGAGGGAGUCAAGGUGUGACCGUCGACCACAGCCAGUGUCAGGCCUCUGCCUCUGGGCCUUUGCUUUGUGGCCUCACUGCAACACAAAGCUCCACCAGGAGGCUGGUUCACGUCCCCUACCACGGAAGCGAGGUCCCAGAAGGCCAGCGGUGGUUCCAGGAGCAACAGCUCCCAAACCCUGAGCAAGGCAACCGAUCGCCAGGACCAGGAAGCAUCACCCAGGAGAUUUGGCGCCCACUUCCACCUCUUCUCUCAGUUUUGGACAAGUGACAAACCAUUUUGCCCCCUCACUCUUCUUUUUUAACUGUUAAACCAAAGGAAAGCACAAAUGAAGGAAAUCCUGUGUAAAGCAUUGAGAAGGAAAGAAGCCUGGAGCAGCCUCUCCUGUCCACAGCCAGGGGUUAGGUCUGCAGGCCCGUCUGCGGUCCCCAUCGAGCAUCAAGGGGACGCUGUGUGUGCUGCAAGUGACCCCGAAAACAACCACAGCCGUCACAUGGUCCUCCUGAAGUUGGGGCACCCUCCUCUCAGCACCAAAAUGGCCCCCACUCCUUCGUGUCCUCCCGCUAUCUCCAAAUCGGACGUUCUUUCUAGCUGAGAUUUUUAUUUUUCCACAUCUGUAGUGCCAUGAAGCGAUUCUGUCUUUGACUUCCAAUGGCAAACCUGGGUGAUCGGGAACAAGCACGUUGUACCCUUGGCUGGACAUGGCCAAGACACAAGGCAUUCCACGGCGGCAAGCUGACCGCACAGCAGUCUGGCUUGAUUUUCAGCCGUCAUCAUUGGGUUCUGUUUUGACAGCUCUGCUGUCCCAUAGGGACUGCGACUGGGACCAGGUCAACCACGCCAGGGGGGUGUCACCAGCCUUUUCUUUUUUUCUUUCUUUUUUUUUUUUUCCUCCUUAAGCUGCUGUCAAUCCAAACCAUUGGCAUCAUCGUUUCUUUUGAAUUAAAACCAACAUAUCAGCAAUAGUCUGCUCUCCCCGGGAAUCUCUAACAUGCUCUGUUUACAUCGAUAAAUGCACUUAAGGAAAACAAACAAAUUAAAGCUCAUCUUAAAGUCCAAGGAUUUUUAUGUCCACAUUUUCCCUGUAGGCCACACGGACAUGGCCAGGUGCUGGGGGUGGGUCUGGACAAGAUGGUAGAGCCCAUGGAUUACCCCAUCGAGCGGCCACCUCAGAGGAGAUGCCACCCAUCAUCAAAAGACUAAAUUGGGAAAAGAAGCCUCCUGGCUUGGUGCAGUGGCUCACACCUGUAAUCCCAGCACUCUGGGAGGCCAAGGCGGGCUGAUCACUUGAGCUCAGGUGUUCGAGACCAGCCUGGCCAACAUGGUGAGCCUGCGUCACCUGGCUUCUGGCACACAGCUCGGCCACUGUGUCCCUCCUGCCUCCCUGGCAGGUCCUUCUAGGGGCCCUCUCCUGGCUGGCUUUCCAGGGCAUUCCUUCCACUCUAUCCAGGGUCCUUCCCAAGACCACACCCAGGUCCAGUCAUUCCCUAGGACUUGGCAGAGAGCUGUACUCACAGCCAAGAUCACAGCAAAAUCAGCAAAGGGAAAAGGCAUGCAGAGUGAAGUCCAGAGGCAACCAGACAGAAGCAUCCAGAAUCCUCUCACAGUGGGGUCACACACCCCAUGCUUAACUCCCCCAACAAUGAGUUGUAACAACA